UGGCUACAUGCGCCUGGUGGUACGCGAGUUGGAGAGCCAGUUGCAGGACGCACGCCAGAGCCUGGCUUUGCAACGCCGCUCAUCCUGGAAGUCUGUUGCCAGCCGCUGUAAGCCCCAGGCUCCUAACCACCGAGCUGCGGGCCUGGAGAAUGGCCACUGCCUCUCCAAGGACAGCAGCCCUGUGGGCUUGGUUGAAGAAGCGGGCAGCAGGUCUGCAGGGUGGGGGUUGGCUGAGUGGGAGCUGCAGGGCCCUGCCAGCCUCCUCCUAGGCAAGGGGCAGAGCCCUGUGUCCCCUGAGACCUCCUGCUUCUCUACCCUGCAUGACUGGUAUGGCCAGGAGAUCGUGGAGCUGCGGCAGUGUUGGCAGAAGAGGGCCCAGGGGAGCCACUCAAAAUGUGAGGAACAGGAUAGGCCCUAAGUCUGGGCCCUUUGAGUCAGGAAACCAGGGCCAGUUCUUUUUCAGGAGUUAAAUGUUUACCCAUUUCCAAGGUUGCGUUUUGGGAGGGGACAUGGGUUCUCUCCUUCCUGCUAUUUAGGCAUUCUCCAGGUUCGAGAUCCACCCGUGUGUCUGGAAGGGACUGCGGGACCAUUCCUUCCAUCCUCUUUAUUUCCUGAGGUCCAGAGAAGGAAGGAGACUUAGCAGCCACAGAGCAAGACCCCAAUCUCCUGACUGCACUGGCCUGACUGCCCCCUCCCAGGGGAUGUUAAUGAAAUGAAGGAAGUGGGGAAUGUCACCCGAGACUGUCACAGGCUUGCCAUACCUUUGGCCUACACACCGGGCUCUAGAGCCAUAAUUUCCAACCUGGGGAGUCUCCUGUGCACUUAAAUCCGAGGUAGGCUGCAGUAUCGGCUUGAAGCUCUGACACUGUCAGAGAAAGUGGAUUUAUUGUGUCAUAGGAGUUUCUGGGACCCAGCUCUUCCUGAGAGGGGUGGGAAGAUUGGGGAUGGGAUCCUCACUCAGCAGUCUGGGUAGGGCCCUUUGAGGCAGAGGGUCUUCGGCCAGUGAAGAGAGAUUUAUUCUGCUCAGAGUGCUGGGGUCCCAUCCUUUCUCCCUGGCUGCCCUGUUAACAGAUGGUGCUGGACCUUGCCCCGGAAGGGGCUUGUAGCUUUUUUACGUCAACGAAAUGCCCUCCUGUACUCUGUCUUCAGCAGCCAACUCCUGGAGCUGCCAAGUGAGGGGUUAAAGAAGAGGUGGGGAGGCAGUGUGGCUCCCUGGGAAAAGUCUGUUGCUUUGGUUCUCAGUCCUGGGUAUUCUAGGAGCUUGGACACGGGAUUGCGUUUCCUGUGCUAAAAUUCUCUCUCCUGGCUGGGCUCCGGUAAACUGAAGCUGCUCGAGAAAUCACCUGGGAACUCUCAUAGCCGUUUGUCACCCAGGGUGUACUUGCCAGGACCUCUCCUUGCUACUCUUCCCAAAGUCGGGAGGCAAAGCGGCUGGGUCACCAGAGCCUGACCAUACUGACGCUCCAGGGGGAAGACGCAGAGGCCGGGAAGAGACACCCCCUCCCAAACACAUAAAACUUGCCCCUUCCUAGCCUCGGCUCCCCUCACUGGGGCCUUGGGCAGGACCGACCCGCAUCCAACUAGGCCUAAGGGGUAGGCUCUGAGCCUCUUACCCCUAAGAGGCGGAGAUGCGCCCAAGGCGGGCGCCCGGCCUGUUCCCCAGCCCUGCCUGGAAGCCCCGCAGCCACUGCAUUUUGUUUAAACACAGAUAGCACGGGCCUUUCUCUUAUUGCUACAGUGUUUUGUACACGGUUAAAACACUAGUAAAGCUUUUUCGUUAUUA